AGCCCCGGCUCCUAGGCUGACAGACCAGCCCAGAUCCAGUGGCCCGGAGGGGCCUGAGCUAAAUCCGCAGGACCUGGGUAACACGAGGAAGGUAAAGAGUUCCUGUCCUCGCCCCUCCCCACCCCCACCUUUUCUGUGAUCUUUUCAGCCUUUCGCUGGUGACUUGUUCUUCCAGGGCCCAUUUCUCUACCCUACCUGGGUUUCUUCUAACCUGGAAAUCUAAUGAUCAAAUCACACUAAAAAGUCAGUAGCUCCUGUGGAUUACAUAUCCCAGGAGCAUAUAGAUUUUGAAUUUUGAAUUUUGAAAGAAAUUCUGCGUGGAGAUAAUAUUGAGGCAGAGACACUGCUAGUGGUCUGAAGAUUUGAAAGGACCACUUUCUGUGUGCAGGCAGGGCCUCAGCUGGAGAUAGAUGGGUCUGGGCGAGGCAGGAGAGUGACAAGUUCUGAGGUGAAAUGAAGGAAGCCCUCAGAGAAUGCUCCUCCCACCUUGAAUCUCAUCCCCAGGGUCUCACUGUCCCAUUCUUGGUGCUGGGUGGAUCCAAAUCCAGGAGAUGGGGCAAGCAUCCUGGGAUGGCUGAGGGCACACUCUGGCAGAUUCUGUGUGUGUCCUCAGAUGCUCAGCCACAGACCUUUGAGGGAGUAAAGGGGGCAGACCCACCCACCUUGCCUCCAGGCUCUUUCCUUCCUGGUCCUGUUCUAUGGUGGGGCUCCCUUGCCAGACUUCAGACUGAGAAGUCAGAUGAAGUUUCAAGAAAAGGAAAUUGUCGGUUUGGUCCCUUUAGGGCUCCGGAUAUCUUUGGUGACUUGUCCACUCCAGUGUGGCAUCAUGUGGCAGCUGCUCCUCCCAACUGCUCUGCUACUUCUAGUUUCAGCUGGCAUGCGGACUGAAGAUCUCCCAAAGGCUGUGGUGUUCCUGGAGCCUCAAUGGUACAGGGUGCUCGAGAAGGACAGUGUGACUCUGAAGUGCCAGGGAGCCUACUCCCCUGAGGACAAUUCCACACAGUGGUUUCACAAUGAGAGCCUCAUCUCAAGCCAGGCCUCGAGCUACUUCAUUGACGCUGCCACAGUCGACGACAGUGGAGAGUACAGGUGCCAGACAAACCUCUCCACCCUCAGUGACCCGGUGCAGCUAGAAGUCCAUAUCGGCUGGCUGUUGCUCCAGGCCCCUCGGUGGGUGUUCAAGGAGGAAGACCCUAUUCACCUGAGGUGUCACAGCUGGAAGAACACUGCUCUGCAUAAGGUCACAUAUUUACAGAAUGGCAAAGGCAGGAAGUAUUUUCAUCAUAAUUCUGACUUCUACAUUCCAAAAGCCACACUCAAAGACAGCGGCUCCUACUUCUGCAGGGGGCUUUUUGGGAGUAAAAAUGUGUCUUCAGAGACUGUGAACAUCACCAUCACUCAAGGUUUGGCAGUGUCAACCAUCUCAUCAUUCUUUCCACCUGGGUACCAAGUCUCUUUCUGCUUGGUGAUGGUACUCCUUUUUGCAGUGGACACAGGACUAUAUUUCUCUGUGAAGACAAACAUUCGAAGCUCAACAAGAGACUGGAAGGACCAUAAAUUUAAAUGGAGAAAGGACCCUCAAGACAAAUGACCCCCAUCCCAUGGGGGUAAUAAGAGCAGUAGCAGCAGCAUCUCUGAACAUUUCUCUGGAUUUGCAACCCCAUCAUCCUCAGGCCUCUCUACAAGCAGCAGGAAACAUAGAACUCAGAGCCAGAUCCCUUAUCCAACUCUCGACUUUUCCUUGGUCUCCAGUGGAAGGGAAAAGCCCAUGAUCUUCAAGCAGGGAAGCCCCAGUGAGUAGCUGCAUUCCUAGAAAUUGAAGUUUCAGAGCUACACAAACACUUUUUCUGUCCCAACCGUUCCCUCACAGCAAAGCAACAAUACAGGCUAGGGAUGGUAAUCCUUUAAACAUACAAAAAUUGCUCGUGUUAUAAAUUACCCAGUUUAGAGGGGAAAAAAAAACAAUUAUUCCUAAAUAAAUGGAUAAGUAGAAUUAAUGGUUGAGGCAGGACCAUACAGAGUGUGGGAACUGCUGGGGAUCUAGGGAAUUCAGUGGGACCAAUGAAAGCAUGGCUGAGAAAUAGCAGGUAGUCCAGGAUAGUCUAAGGGAGGUGUUCCCAUCUGAGCCCAGAGAUAAGGGUGUCUUCCUAGAACAUUAGCCGUAGUGGAAUUAACAGGAAAUCAUGAGGGUGACGUAGAAUUGAGUCUUCCAGGGGACUCUAUCAGAACUGGACCAUCUCCAAGUAUAUAACGAUGAGUCCUCUUAAUGCUAGGAGUAGAAAAUGGUCCUAGGAAGGGGACUGAGGAUUGCGGUGGGGGGUGGGGUGGAAAAGAAAGUACAGAACAAACCCUGUGUCACUGUCCCAAGUUGCUAAGUGAACAGAACUAUCUCAGCAUCAGAAUGAGAAAGCCUGAGAAGAAAGAACCAACCACAAGCACACAGGAAGGAAAGCGCAGGAGGUGAAAAUGCUUUCUUGGCCAGGGUAGUAAGAAUUAGAGGUUAAUGCAGGGACUGUAAAACCACCUUUUCUGCUUCAAUAUCUAAUUCCUGUGUAGCUUUGUUCAUUGCAUUUAUUAAACAAAUGUUGUAUAACCAAUACUAAAUGUACUACUGAGCUUCGCUGAGUUAAGUUAUGAAACUUUCAAAUCCUUCAUCAUGUCAGUUCCAAUGAGGUGGGGAUGGAGAAGACAAUUGUUGCUUAUGAAAGAAAGCUUUAGCUGUCUCUGUUUUGUAAGCUUUAAGCGCAACAUUUCUUGGUUCCAAUAAAGCAUUUUACAAGAUCUUGCAUGCUACUCUUAGAUAGAAGAUGGGAAAACCAUGGUAAUAAAAUAUGAAUGAUAAAA